AGCUGACUGUUCGGCCGCCACCGCCGCUGCCGCUGCCGCUGUCGCUGUCGCCGCCGCCGCCGCCCGCCGCCGCCGCCGCCGCCGCCGCCGCUGCCAUGGCUCAAUACAAGGGCGCCGCGAGCGAGGCCGGCCGCGCCAUGCACCUGAUGAAGAAGCGGGAGAAGCAGCGCGAGCAGAUGGAGCAGAUGAAGCAGCGCAUCGCGGAGGAGAACAUCAUGAAAUCCAACAUUGACAAGAAGUUCUCUGCGCACUACGACGCGGUGGAGGCAGAGCUCAAGUCCAGCACCGUGGGUCUCGUGACCCUGAAUGACAUGAAGGCCAAGCAGGAGGCUCUGGUGAAGGAGCGGGAGAAGCAGCUGGCCAAGAAGGAGCAGUCCAAGGAGCUGCAGAUGAAGCUGGAGAAGCUUCGAGAGAAGGAGCGUAAGAAGGAAGCCAAGCGGAAGAUCUCCAGCCUGUCCUUCACCCUGGAGGAGGAAGAAGAGGGAGGCGAGGAGGAAGAGGAGGCGGCCAUGUAUGAGGAGGAGAUGGAAAGGGAAGAGAUCACCACGAAGAAGAGAAAACUGGGGAAGAACCCAGACGUUGACACAAGCUUCUUGCCUGAUCGAGACCGUGAGGAGGAGGAGAAUCGGCUUCGGGAAGAGCUGCGGCAGGAGUGGGAAGCCAAGCAGGAGAAGAUCAAGAGUGAGGAGAUCGAGAUCACCUUCAGCUACUGGGAUGGCUCUGGGCACCGGCGGACAGUCAAGAUGAGAAAGGGCAACACCAUGCAGCAGUUCCUGCAGAAGGCGCUCGAGAUCCUUCGGAAAGACUUCAGUGAGCUGAGGUCCGCAGGGGUGGAGCAGCUCAUGUACAUCAAGGAGGACUUGAUCAUCCCUCACCAUCACAGCUUCUACGACUUCAUCGUCACCAAGGCACGGGGGAAGAGUGGACCACUCUUCAACUUUGAUGUUCAUGACGAUGUGCGGUUGCUCAGUGACGCCACUGUGGAGAAGGAUGAGUCCCAUGCAGGCAAGGUGGUGCUGAGGAGCUGGUACGAGAAGAACAAGCACAUCUUUCCCGCCAGCCGCUGGGAACCCUACGACCCUGAAAAGAAGUGGGACAAGUACACGAUCCGCUGAGCAUCCAGGAGGCUGCGCGGCCCCGGCUCCUCAGCUCCCUCAGUGUGCCCCGUGGUGUCACCGGGACUCCAGGCACCCGCUCCCCUGCGACCAUGCCAGGCACGCUGGGAGGAGGACGGCAGCUGCUCGUGUCCUGCCCCUGCCACAUCAGUGACUGCUUUAUUCUUUUCCAAUAAAGAAGUGCACGUGUCAGAGCUGGAGCGCCUGCAUUGUGAGAAACCA